UUUAAUGUCCUUUUGUUCAUGCAAAGAAGGAUUAACUAUCUCAACCUGCCAGAAUUGAGUUGCUUUGGGACUCAAUUGAGUUGCUUUGUUGAUUAUGCCAAUGGUUGAUUUAAACAUACAUCCCCAAUAGUGCUUUCCCAUAAGCAGAAUUCUGCAGAAUAUAAAAGAACAACAUAAAACAAAAAUAGACACAGCUUAAUCUCCUCCCAGCAAUGGGAGAACUAGACAAGGACUAGCGACCUAAGUGCCAUGGUCCUGCAUACAGAUUUAAAGAAAGGGACAAUGUUUGCUAACUAGAGUUUCCUGAUCACUUUGAUAGAUCAUCAUCUGUUGGGGACUGGGGUUUCUGUUAAGUGAAAUGUUAGGUUUAGAUCUUCAGACUGCUAGAGAGAUUCACUGUUAGUUUGGUAAUCCUCCUUCCUUUUUUUCAGUGGGAAAUCUAAACGGAAUUACUAUUUUUGUUUUGCUUGACAUUUUCAUUCUUUCCCUGCCCCCACGCACUUGAAUAGGGUAAAAAGAGGAGUAAGAGAGUGGUAGAUGAUUAGAGCCUAUAUUACUCUUUAAGAAUUUUUUAAUCAAAGCCCAGCUAAAGAGUGAAAAUUACAGAGCCUUGGCAGAGCUGAAUUAACACUGAUUCUACCAGUGGGUAACAGUGCCAGAUAUCUCAUGGGGGAAGUCUGUAUGAAUACUGAAUUUAUGAACCUAAAUUAGGAAUGAGAGCUUGCUUGUCAAAGAAAAGAGAAGUAUGUGAAGAAGCAGCCCAUUCAGGAAACUUUAAUAAAAUGUGGGUAAAACAAAUUAUACAUCAUCACUGGCAAUUUGAUCAAUAUUUGCGUUGCAUUCAAAAUCUAUUGGCAUAAACUACCUGUUCAAACGUUUUAUUUCCAGUCUUUAAGAUAGAGCUUUCCCUUCUUAUAUGCCAAGCAAGGAAAUGUAAUUGAGCUGCCCUGCAGGCAAGUGGAAUUGAAUGUACAUGACAAAUUUUAUGUUAAGCUUACUAUGAAAUUGUACACAUCAUGCUACAGAGAUAGUAUCAUCAAUUUCACUGUAAAUGAAAAAUGCAAGUCAUGAGUUUGUAUUCUAUAAACUAAUAGCUCAUAUAAUACUUGGCCUAGGUAAUAAUCUUUGCUUCUGGGGAACAUACAGCAUGCCAGGAUAUGCUACUAGAACGAAAAAGUUGUUUUCCAUGGUUGAGGUUUUUGUUCAUUUGUUUUUUUAAGUGAUUCACAUGCAAGGAUACGAUGCACAAAGCUCAUAUCGUUAAAAUUCUUUGCCAAAACCAAAAUUACCCGAGGACAGUGUUAUUUCACCAUACAAUAUAAGCACAGGCUAUUCAGGGCUUGCCACUGGAAAUGGACUCAGUGACUCACCUGCAGGGUCAAAGGAUCAUGGCAGUGUGCCCAUUAUUGUACCUUUAAUUCCACCACCUUUCAUAAAGCCACCAGCAGAAGAUGAUGUGUCAAAUGUACAAAUAAUGUGUGCCUGGUGCCAGAAAGUGGGAAUCAAGCGCUAUUCCCUGAGUAUGGGAAGUGAGGUGAAAAGCUUCUGCAGCGAGAAGUGCUUUGCGGCCUGCCGACGAGCCUACUUCAAGAGAAAUAAGGCUAGAGAUGAAGAUGGACAUGCUGAAAAUUUUCCCCAGCAGCACUAUGCUAAGGAAACUCCAAGGCUUGCCUUCAAGAAUAACUGCGAACUACUUGUAUGUGACUGGUGUAAGCACAUAAGACACACAAAAGAAUACCUGGAUUUUGGGGACGGGGAAAGAAGGCUUCAGUUCUGCAGUGCAAAAUGUCUCAAUCAAUACAAAAUGGACAUUUUCUACAAAGAGACCCAGGCCAAUCUUCCAGCUGGGCUGUGCAGCACAUUACACCCUCCCAUGGAAAAUAAAGCAGAAGGCACCGGGGUGCAGCUGCUCACUCCAGACUCUUGGAAUAUCCCGCUAACAGAUGCUCGGAGGAAGGCCCCCUCCCCGGUGGCUACAGCUGGCCAAAGCCAGGGCCCUGGCCCGUCGGCGUCCACCACCGUCUCUCCAUCUGACACUGCCAACUGCUCUGUCACUAAAAUCCCCACGCCAGUGCCCAAGUCCAUCCCCAUCAGCGAGACUCCAAAUAUCCCUCCUGUCUCCGUCCAGCCACCUGCUAGCAUCGGGCCUCCCCUUGGCGUCCCGCCUCGGAGCCCUCCCAUGGUGAUGACCAACCGCGGCCCGGUGCCGCUGCCCAUCUUCAUGGAGCAGCAGAUCAUGCAGCAGAUCCGCCCGCCCUUCAUCCGCGGGCCUCCGCACCAUGCCUCCAACCCCAACAGCCCCCUGUCCAACCCCAUGCUUCCCGGCAUCGGGCCCCCGCCCGGUGGCCCCAGAAACCUGGGCCCCACUUCCAGCCCCAUGCACCGGCCCAUGCUAUCGCCCCACAUCCACCCCCCGAGCACCCCCACCAUGCCCGGGAACCCCCCAGGCCUGCUGCCCCCGCCGCCUCCGGGCGCCCCGCUGCCGAGUCUUCCCUUCCCGCCAGUGAGCAUGAUGCCAAAUGGCCCGAUGCCGGUGCCCCAGAUGAUGAAUUUCGGGCUGCCGUCGCUUGCCCCGCUGGUGCCGCCCCCGACCCUGCUCGUGCCGUACCCCGUGAUCGUGCCCCUACCGGUGCCCAUCCCCAUCCCCAUCCCUAUCCCUCACGUCAGCGACUCCAAGCCCCCCAACGGGUUCUCCAGCAACGGGGAGAACUUCAUUCCGAACGCCCCUGGCGACUCCGCGGCGGCGGGCGGCAAGCCAAGCGGACACUCCCUGUCCCCCCGGGACUCCAAGCAGGGCUCGUCCAAGUCCGCGGACUCGCCCCCCGGCUGCUCGGGCCAGGCCCUGAGCCUGGCGCCCACGCCCGCCGAGCAUGGCCGGAGCGAGGUGGUGGACCUGACGCGGCGCGCCGGCAGCCCCCCGGGCCCCCCGGGCGCGGGCGGCCAGCUCGGCUUCCCAGGCGUGCUGCAGGGCCCGCAGGACGGCGUCAUCGACCUGACCGUGGGCCACCGAGCCCGGCUGCACAACGUGAUCCACCGCGCGCUGCACGCGCACGUCAAGGCGGAGCGCGAGCCGAGCGCCGCGGAGCGCAGGACCUGCGGCGGCUGCAGGGACGGCCACUGCAGCCCGCCCGCCGCCGGCGACCCAGGCCCGGGCGCCCCGGCGGGCCCCGAGGCGGCCGCGGCCUGCAACGUCAUCGUGAACGGCACGCGCGGCGCCGCCGCCGAGGGCGCUAAGAGCGCGGAGCCGCCUCCCGAGCAGCCGCCGCCGCCGCCGCCGCCCGCGCCCCCCAAGAAGCUGCUGUCGCCUGAGGAACCGGCGGUGAGCGAGCUAGAGUCGGUCAAGGAGAAUAACUGUGCUUCCAACUGCCACCUGGACGGGGAGGCGGCCAAAAAGCUGAUGGGCGAGGAGGCCCUGGCGGGGGGCGACAAGUCAGACCCGAACCUUAAUAACCCCGCGGACGAGGACCAUGCCUAUGCUCUGCGGAUGCUGCCCAAGACCGGCUGCGUGAUCCAGCCUGUGCCAAAACCCGCGGAGAAGGCUGCCAUGGCACCGUGCAUCAUCUCCUCGCCCAUGCUCAGCGCCGGGCCUGAGGACCUGGAGCCGCCGCUCAAAAGGAGGUGCCUCCGAAUUAGAAAUCAGAAUAAGUAAAAGAUGUACCCAUAACCUUCCAUCUUCAGCAGGACUGGGACUAGAGUGAAGCAAAGGAAGGGCUUAGGGCAGAGACUUUGAGGAGGCACCCACUCAGGGUCAUGCUAGUGCAGCACUGGUCCUGGCUCUGUCUCCAGAUCCAUAUGGCAGCUCCCUAAAGCUGGUCUCCUGGCCCCCUGGACUCGUCCCUGGAUGGCCUUCAGCAACUCCCCCUGAAAUUUCAUGGAAAGUUUUAUGUGCCUAUGCACAGAGGCAUUUUCAUGGGAGAAGACGUCCAUAGAUUUUGGCUCCAGAAAAAGUAUGCUCUAUAUCUCUGAAGGAUUAUCUUACCUUAUUAUGGAGCAAUAUCUGAGUUGAAAUUUUUCUUGUUUCUCUGAGGAAGCUGAAUUAAUGGAAAGUUUCUCUUAAAACUUAGAAUAUAUUGUUUGGCAAUUUCUGCUGUGGGCCUAAUAUUGCAGAAUCAAAGUUGGAGCUACAUCAUGUAGCACUUGCCUCAAUAAGAUUGCCUUAGUGACACAAUGCAAAAGGUUACAGACUUUUCUUCAAGUUACCAUUUCCCACAAGGGCCUGUGAUGAAAGAAGAAAAGAGAAGCAAGAAAAGAAAUAAGCUAGAUACUUCCCCAGCACUUGGACCUUCAAAAUUUGUACGAUACAGGGAGACACUGUUCUUCUGUGGAAAGAUCUUCUACUCUGCCACUGAGGCCAAGAAAGCAGAAUGGCCAGAGUCAGAGAGGUGGACAGGUCGGUGAACACCAGGGCAUUGAUGUGGCAGUGUCUGGGAGCGCUGCCAAUGCUCCCUAGCUCCCCAGUAUGCCUCUUUACUUGGAGAGACUGCACUUGGAAAGAGACGCGUUCGGCCAGCUAUUAACCAGCCGUUGCCCAGGAGGGCACUGGAAAUCAGUUCCCUGACUGGUUUCCAAUGAGUCACUCCCUUGCCAGCCUAAGCUGCUGCCUGUGCACCAUGUUCAAUCAUUUACACCUACCUUCAUGCAGACAAGUGCUGCAGAGGGGCAGAGAUGUCUGAGGACCAAAAUACGCUGCACCGUGGAACACUUACCUCAUGUUGUGGAACACUUACCCUCACCCGAACGCCCCGCCUUUUCCAGACUUUCCUGUCUAAGAGAUCGUGCCAAAGGGACGGGGGUGGCCAUGCUGUUUUCUCUUACCGUGUCCUGCACAACUUAUUUUGUAUCCUUCCGUUGCCGUUUUAAGUGCAUAGCACUUUCUAUGUGGAUGGAUGUUAAGGCAAUGCAUUCUGCAUGUGUAAACUUUUUCUUAGGGCCUCAAAGGGCAUAAACGAAAUUCAUUCAGAGAAAGAAAGAAAUUAGCUUUAGAAAAUAAACAAUUUAGCACUGGCAUCGUUUAACAGGGUCCCAUUCUCAAGGAAAUGGGGUAAAUGCCAUUUCAGACACCAGCUCUGAAUACUAACUGCAGAGAGUUCUUCUCCAGAUUUGUGGAUUUCCACAGCACAGAAAAAAAAAAUAGGGUGGGGUCAGGAUUGGGAACAUGAGACCAUCAACAGGGAGGGGAAGUACACACACAUGCACAAAACUUAUUUCAAGGGUCAUCGAAAAGAUUCUAGUGAAAAAUGACUGGAGCAAAAGAAAAUGACAAUAACAAAAACUUGGAAUUAUUCUCUAAUGCUUUAAAAUAGUCCCAAGUGUACUACAUAGUUUAAAAUUGGAAAUCAGUCAAGUUACCUAACUCUGCCACUCCUUGGACUGAAUUAAUGAUCAUAAGCAAAAAAUGCUUGUGCAAUUGUACUGUGUGGUCCAGAUGUACAGCCCUGAGUAGAGAGAUGGGGGCAGAGCAGACCUGGCUUUCCAGGUAGCCAAGGGGUCAGGGCUGGGGCAAAUCAAAGCUUCCAGUGCUCCCAGCCUCAUUCCCAUCCAGAUAUUUGGCUGCACCAGCACUAGUUGUCUCAUCAUUUUCCCCUCUGAACCUCUGGUUUGUUGUCUGUCUUUGAUAUAGUAAGCUGUGUUUUGUUUUGGGUAAAAAGGGAAGUAAGAAUGUGACUGAUAGUAUUUAAAGAACAAAAGGGAGAAACGCUUCAUGAAUUCAUUUGAUAUGGAACAUUGACCUAACAUCCAAAAAAAUACAACUAAAAAGUAGAUCUUUCCCUCAUUUGCAUGGCUUAUUUCCCCAGAUAUGUUUUUGGUAUUGAAAAUGAAUGGUAUUCCCAUACAACAUGUGUCUCAAUUUGUAAUGAUAUCCUCCUUGCAGCUGGCUUAGUUCUGCAAGUGUUUCUAAAAUGUUACUGUCUUAAAUUUGAACCAACCUACAAUAACAAAUUAUCUAGAAGCAAAGUGGCUAAACGGCAUUUGGAGAGAGAAGGGGAAACCCUAUAUUUCAUCCUUCAACUCUUGUUUUAGAAAUUCAGACUGUAACGUGAUCUUUUUCUAAAGAAAUCUACACACACACACUUUAAAAACUGUGCAGCUUGGGUGUUGUGGGAGCAAGAAUGAUCAGGUUUAAGUUUCUCUGCAAAGCUCUGCAUCCCAUCAACAAGCUCUUUUGAUAUUUUAAACCCGUAUUUAGAGUAAUUUCAAGAUAUUUGGAGCACAUGUGGUUACAUGUAAAACUUUGUCCUUAUAAUGUGUUAGAUGCUCAUACUUUAAAUAUUUAUAAGCUUUUAUUUAUUUAUUUAUUUUUAUUUUUUUCUGAGAUGGAGUUUCACUCUGUUGCCCGGCUGGAGUGCAGUGACGCGAUCUCGGCCCACUAUAACCUCUGCCUUCUGGGUUCAAGCAAUUCUCCUGCCUCAGCCUCCCAAGUAGCUGGGAUUACAGGCGCGCACCACCAUGUCCAGCUAAUUUUUUUUUGUAUUUUUAGUAGAGAUGGGGUUUCACCCUGUUGGCUAGGAUGGUCUCCAUCUCUUGACCUCAUCAUCCACCUGUCUAGGCCUCCCAAAGUGCUGGGAUUACAGGUAUGAGCCACCAUGCCCAGCCUUUAUAAGCCAUUUUUAAGUAAUUUACCCAAAAGCUUUCUCCCACUAGAAUACUAUAAUUGAGUAGUAUCUGAGCAUCAUUAUAGAAGAUACAAGAUGAAGUUGCUGCAGCAUGCAUUCACAUUCUUCUUGCUUUUCUGGUUUUAAUUCAAAUGUCAUUUUUAGUAGAAUCAGCUUAUUUUAUUAUUUUUUAAAUGUAUUAAAAAAUCAUAAACAAGA